GUUGCAUUUUGUUUAGUACAAGACAUGUCUGGGCGCGGCAAAGGCGGGAAGGGUCUGGGCAAAGGAGGCGCUAAGCGCCACCGCAAAGUUCUGCGCGACAACAUUCAGGGCAUCACCAAGCCCGCCAUCCGACGCCUGGCACGGCGUGGAGGCGUUAAGCGCAUCUCAGGCCUUAUAUACGAGGAGACACGCGGAGUUCUUAAAGUGUUUUUGGAGAAUGUAAUCCGCGAUGCAGUUACCUACACGGAGCACGCCAAACGCAAGACAGUCACAGCCAUGGACGUGGUUUACGCGCUCAAGCGCCAGGGCCGCACCCUGUAUGGCUUUGGCGGCUGAGUGUUUUACUUACUUACACGGUUCCUCAAAGGCCCUUCUCAGGGCCACCCA